AGGAGAUACUUGAAGGCAGUUUGAAAGACUUGUUUUACAGAUUCUUAGUCCAAAGAUUUCCAAUUAGGGAGAAGAAGCAGCAGAAAAGGAGAAAAGCCAAGUAUGAGUGAUGAUGAGGCCUUCAUCUACUGACAUUUAACCUGGCGAGAACCGUCGAUGGUGAAGUUGCCUUUUCAGCUGGGAGCUGUCCGUUCAGCUUCCGUAAUAAAUGCAGUCAAAGAGGCAGUCCCUUCCCAUUGCUCACAAAGGUCUUGUUUUUGAACCUCGCCCUCACAGAAGCCGUUUCUCAUCAUGCCAAGCCAACAGAAGAAAAUCAUUUUUUGCAUGGCCGGAGUGUUCAGUUUUGCAUGUGCCCUCGGAGUUGUGACAGCCUUGGGGACACCGUUGUGGAUCAAAGCCACUGUCCUCUGCAAAACGGGAGCUCUGCUCGUCAAUGCCUCAGGGCAGGAGCUGGACAAGUUUAUGGGUGAAAUGCAGUACGGGCUUUUCCACGGAGAGGGUGUGAGGCAGUGUGGGUUGGGAGCAAGGCCCUUUCGGUUCUCAUUUUUUCCAGAUUUGCUCAAAGCAAUCCCAGUGAGCAUCCACGUCAAUGUCAUUCUCUUCUCUGCCAUCCUUAUUGUGUUAACCAUGGUGGGGACAGCCUUCUUCAUGUACAAUGCUUUUGGAAAACCUUUUGAAACUCUGCAUGGUCCCCUAGGGCUGUACCUUUUGAGCUUCAUUUCAGUUGCCCUUUGGCUGCCAGCUACCAGGCACCAGGCUCAAGGCUCCUGUGGCUGUCUUGUCAUGAUAUUGUUUGCCUCUGAAGUGAAAAUCCAUCACCUCUCAGAAAAAAUUGCAAAUUAUAAAGAAGGGACUUAUGUCUACAAAACGCAAAGUGAAAAAUAUACCACCUCAUUCUGGGUCAUUUUCUUUUGCUUUUUUGUUCAUUUUCUGAAUGGGCUCCUAAUACGACUUGCUGGAUUUCAGUUCCCUUUUGCAAAAUCUAAAGACGCAGAAACAACUAAUGUAGCUGCAGAUCUAAUGUACUGAAAGGCAAACCUUUCUAUAAUUUUACAAGGGAGUAGACUUGCUUUGGUCACUUUUAGAUGUGGUUAAUUUUGCAUAUCCUUUUAGUCUGCAUAUAUUAAAGCAUCAGGACCCUUCGUGACAAUGUUUACAAAUUACGUACUAAGGAUACAGGCUGGAAAGUAAGGGAAGCAGAAGGAAGGCUUUGAAAAGUUGUUUUAUCUGGUGGGAAAUUGCUUGACCCAGGUAGUCAAAGGCAGUUGACUAGAAUCGACAAAUUGUUACUCCAUAUAUAUAUAUGUGUGUGUGUGUGUGUGUGUGUGUGUGUAAGAUGUCUUCCUAUCAAAAAGAUAUCAAAGGCACAUGGAAUAUAUUUUAAUAAAAACAAAUAAUAUCUCUAAUAUAUCCACACAUUUGUUGCCAGAUUUCAGAAAACUGAGCUGCAAUCGCUUUCCUAAAACAGUAGUGUAUUAAAUGAACAUCUAUAAAAUGUAUCAACACACAUUUUAAAAAAUUUGUUUAAAGUAUACUCUUAGGCCAGGCGUGGUGACUCACACCUGUAAUUCCAGCACUUCAGGAGGCCAAGGUGGGAAGAUCAUUUGAGUUCAGGAGUUCGAGUUACAGCCUGGGCAAUAAAGUGAGACCCUGUCACUAACAAAAUUAAAAAAUAAAAUAAAUAUAAAAUAUAGGCUUUAAAAAAGCAUAGUCUUAUUAACCAUGUCUGUUGGUCAAAAUCUGCAAACUCUAAAAGAAGAAAAGAAGAAAAAACCAAGCUUAGGGUAUUUUUCCUCCCGUGCCUGAGUCCCAAUUACAUUCACGACAGUACUUUCAAUGAACAUAAUUGUUAGGACCACUGAGGAAUCAUGAAAAAUGAUCUCUGCUUAGUACAUUUGAUGCAAAAUGACUUAUUAGGGGCUGUUUUUCUAGCUAUAGUGUCUCGAGUACUAAUAUGCAAUUAUGAAAAUUAUAUUAAAUCUGGGAUUAUGACGGUAUCACUGUAUCAUCUUGGUCUUGUUCUGGCUGUCACCAAGCAUGACCCAGGUCAACUUUUUUUUUCCCCUGAAUUACCCAUCAAAUUGAUCUGCAGCUGACUAAAGGCCACAGCUGAGCCUGGAACUGACCCUUCCUUCAUCCUCAACCUGCUGUCCUCCAGAAAGCACCAAGGAAAAAGCAGAGAAUGACAGCAAACAGAUCACUAGGCCUCUGACCACAGGUGCUGAGUACUCAGCAGCCCUCAUAUAAUAGGUUUGAAAGUACUCCUUAAAAUAAAACACUGUUUCCCUUUGGAACUAUUUACAAGGAUGAAACAACCGUAUACCUGAGAAAUAACUUGCUCUGGUGUCAAUUCGCUAUUCGCCAGCAGACAUCAGAACACACCGAGUUUCCAGAUGCU